GCGUAAAGGCCCGGCCCAAGGGAACGUUCAGGGCGUCUCGGCUUUCCCCGCUGCUGCUUCUGCUAGGCCCAGUGCGAGACCAGAGCACGAGCGACUCCCGUCGUCCCCGGCCAGGCAGAUGUUGGCCUAGUCCUGGCGCGAACGAAGCGCGCUAUUUCCCUGCUUCCUCUAGGCCAAGCCUGCUUUACGGCAGGGCCCGCCUCGGGAGCGAGCACAGACCGGGGCAGCGAGGCCAGCCAGGCGCCGACGAGGUCCCCGAACGCGCACGCGCUCCGUUCAGCUCCGGGUGGCGGCCGCCGGAGUAGACGUUAGCCAUGGAAACCGAGAGCUGGCCCGGGCGGGGCCGCGGUGAGCUCGUUAUUCGGCCGCCGCAGCUUUUCUGCCUCCGCAUUCGGGCACUAACCAACCUCCCGGCGGGAGCGCCCAGCCCGAGUUUACCUGCAAAAAUGCGGUCCCUGGGAUGCCUUCGCGUCUUCUCUUCCCUCGGGUGACUUGAGAAACUGCUGUGUUACAGAAAAGCAUGUGACUUUCAGAAUAAUCCCGAGUGAGGAUGAGUCCAGAUGUGCCUCUACUGAAUGAUUACAAGCAGGACUUCUUUCUGAAGCGCUUUCCACAGACUGUUCUUGGAGGCCCUCGAUUCAAAUUAGGCUAUUGUGCCCCUCCUUACAUAUAUGUUAAUCAAAUUAUUCUUUUUCUAAUGCCAUGGGUUUGGGGUGGAGUCGGAACACUUUUAUACCAGUUAGGCAUCCUGAAAGACUAUUAUACAGCAGCACUUUCAGGUGGAUUAAUGCUUUUUACUGCAUUUGUCAUCCAGUUCACAAGUUUAUACGCCAAAAACAAAUCAACAACAGUAGAAAGAAUACUAACCACGGAUAUCUUAGCAGAGGAGGAUGAGCAUGAAUUUACCAGUUGUACUGGUGCUGAGACUGUCAAAUUUCUCAUUCCUGGCAAGAAAUAUGUAGCCAAUACAGUUUUUCAUUCUAUUCUUGCUGGAUUAGCGUGUGGUCUUGGAACAUGGUAUCUGCUCCCAAAUAGAAUAACCUUGCUGUAUGGCAGUACAGGAGGCACUGCUCUACUAUUCUUCUUUGGAUGGAUGACACUAUGUAUAGCAGAAUAUUCUUUAAUUGUAAACACAGCUACAGAGACUGCGACUUUCCAAACACAGGAUACUUAUGAAAUUAUUCCUCUUAUGAGACCUCUUUAUAUUUUUUUCUUUGUUUCUGUGGAUCUGGCACACAGGUUUGUGGUAAAUAUGCCAGCUCUAGAACACAUGAAUCAGAUUUUACACAUCUUGUUUGUAUUUUUACCCUUUCUGUGGGCACUUGGGACUCUGCCCCCACCCGAUGCACUUCUCUUAUGGGCAAUGGAGCAGGUUUUAGAGUUCGGCCUUGGAGGCUCAUCUAUGUCAACCCACUUACGGUUAUUAGUAAUGUUCAUCAUGUCUGCUGGAACAGCUAUAGCAUCAUAUUUCAUUCCAAGCACUGUUGGUGUGGUUCUUUUCAUGACUGGAUUUGGUUUCUUGCUGAGUCUGAACUUAAGUGAUAUGGGUCACAAAAUUGGAACCAAAUCUAAGGAUUUACCCAGUGGUCCGGAAAAACAUUUUUCAUGGAAGGAAUGCCUUUUCUACAUCAUUAUAUUAGUCUUGGCUCUUUUAGAAACUAGCUUGCUUCAUCACUUUGCUGGCUUCUCACAGAUUUCUAAAAGCAAUUCCCAGGCUAUUGUGGGCUAUGGUUUGAUGAUAUUACUUAUAAUACUGUGGAUACUUAGAGAAAUUCAAAGCGUAUAUAUCAUUGGAAUUUUCCGAAAUCCCUUUUAUCCGAAGGAUGUGCAAACUGUGACUGUAUUCUUUGAGAAGCAAACUAGGCUCAUGAAGAUUGGUAUUGUCAGACGGAUUUUGCUAACUUUAGUAUCACCUUUUGCCAUGAUAGCAUUUCUUUCAUUGGACAGUUCCUUACAAGGGCUCCACUCAGUGUCUGUCUGUAUUGGAUUCACAAGAGCCUUUAGAAUGGUAUGGCAGAAUACAGAAAAUGCUUUAUUGGAGACAGUCAUUGUAUCAACAGUACACUUGAUCUCCAGUACAGACAUAUGGUGGAACAGAAGCCUGGAUACAGGACUCAGACUCUUACUGGUUGGUAUCAUACGUGAUCGUUUGAUUCAGUUCAUCUCUAAAUUGCAGUUUGCCGUGACUGUGCUUUUGACAUCAUGGACAGAGAAAAAACAACGUCGAAAAACAACUGCCACUUUAUGUAUACUCAACAUUGUCUUUUCUCCAUUCGUGUUGGUCAUCAUAGUUUUUUCUACACUACUCUCUUCUCCCUUACUCCCUCUUUUCACCCUUCCUGUGUUCUUGGUGGGGUUUCCCCGACCUAUUCAGAGUUGGCCAGGAGCAGCAGGCACCACAGCCUGUGUGUGUGCAGAUACAGUGUACUACUACCAAAUGGUGCCCAGGUUGACUGCUGUACUGCAGACUGCAAUGGCAGCUGGAAGUUUAGGUCUCCUCCUACCUGGAUCUCAUUACUUGGGCCGUUUUCAGGAUCGUUUAAUGUGGAUAAUGAUUCUGGAAUGUGGCUAUACUUACUGCUCUAUUAACAUUAAGGGGUUAGAAUUGCAGGAAACAUCCUGUCAUACUGCAGAAGCUCGCAGAGUUGAUGAAGUUUUUGAAGAUGCUUUUGAGCAAGAAUACACAAGAGUAUGUUCCCUUAAUGAACACUUUGGAAAUGUCUUGACACCCUGUACUGUUUUGCCUGUGAAAUUGUAUUCUGAUGCCAGGAAUGUUCUAUCAGGCAUAAUUGAUUCUCAUGAAAACUUAAAAGAAUUUAAAGGUGACCUCAUUAAAGUACUUGUGUGGAUACUUGUUCAAUACUGCUCCAAAAGGCCUGGCAUGAAAGAGAAUGUUCACAACACUGAAAAUAAAGGGAAAGCACCUCUAAUGUUGCCUGCUUUGAACACUUUGCCACCUCCCAAAUCCCCAGAAGACAUAGACAGUUUAAAUUCAGAAACUUUUAAUGACUGGUCUGAUGAUAAUAUUUUUGAUGAUGAGCCAACUAUCAAAAAAGUAAUAGAAGAAAAACAUCAGUUGAAAGAUUUGCCAGGUACAAAUUUGUUUAUUCCAGGAUCAGUAGAAUCACAGAGGGUUGGUGAUCAUUCUACAGGCACUGUUCCUGAAAACGAUCUUUACAAAGCAGUUCUAUUAGGAUACCCUGCUGUUGACAAAGGAAAACAAGAGGACAUGCCAUAUAUUCCUCUCAUGGAGUUCAGUUGUUCACAUUCUCACUUAGUAUGCUUACCCGCAGAGUGGAGGACUAGCUGUAUGCCCAGUUCCAAAAUGAAGGAGAUGAGCUCGUUAUUUCCAGAAGACUGGUACCAAUUUGUUCUAAGGCAGUUGGAAUGUUAUCAUUCAGAAGAGAAGGCCUCAAAUGUACUGGAAGAAAUUGCCAAGGACAAAGUUUUAAAAGACUUUUAUGUUCAUACAGUAAUGACUUGUUAUUUUAGUUUAUUUGGAAUAGACAAUAUGGCUCCUAGUCCUGGUCAUAUAUUGAGAGUUUACGGUGGUGUUUUGCCUUGGUCUGUUGCUUUGGACUGGCUCACAGAAAAGCCAGAACUGUUUCAACUAGCACUGAAAGCAUUCAGGUAUACUCUGAAACUAAUGAUUGAUAAAGCAAGUUUAGGUCCAAUAGAAGACUUUAGAGAACUGAUUAAGUACCUUGAAGAAUAUGAACGUGACUGGUACAUUGGUUUGGUAUCUGAUGAAAAGUGGAAGGAAGCAAUUUUACAAGAAAAGCCAUACUUGUUUUCUCUGGGGUAUGAUUCUAAUAUGGGAAUUUACACUGGGAGAGUGCUUAGCCUUCAAGAAUUAUUGAUCCAAGUGGGAAAGUUAAAUCCUGAAGCUGUUAGAGGUCAGUGGGCCAAUCUUUCAUGGGAAUUACUUUAUGCCACAAACGAUGAUGAAGAACGUUAUAGUAUACAAGCUCAUCCACUACUUUUAAGAAAUCUUACGGUACAAGCAGCAGAACCUCCCCUGGGAUAUCCGAUUUAUUCUUCAAAACCUCUCCACAUACAUUUGUAUUAGAGCUCAUUUUGACUGUAAUGUCAUCAAAUGCAAUGUUUUUAUUUUUUCAUCCUAAAAAAGUAACUGUGAUUCUUGUAACUUGAGGACUUCUCCACACCCCCAUUCAGAUGCCUGAGAACAGCUAAGCUCCGUAAAGUUGGUUCUCUUAGCCAUCUUAAUGGUUCUAAAAAACAGCAAAAACAUCUUUAUGUCUAAGAUAAAAGAACUAUUUGGCCAAUAUUUGUGCCCUCUGGACUUUAGUAGGCUUUGGUAAAUGUGAGAAAACUUUUGUAGAAUUAUCAUAUAAUGAAUUUUGUAAUGCUUUCUUAAAUGUGUUAUAGGUGAAUUGCCAUACAAAGUUAACAGCUAUGUAAUUUUUACAUACUUAAGAGAUAAACAUAUCAGUGUUCUAAGUAGUGAUAAUGGAUCCUGUUGAAGGUUAACAUAAUGUGUAUAUAUUUGUUUGAAAUAUAAUUUAUAGUAUUUUCAAAUGUGCUGAUUUAUUUUGACAUCUAAUAUCUGAAUGUUUUUGUAUCAAGUAGUUUGUUUUCAUAGACUUCAAUUCAUAAACUUUAAAAAACUUUUAAUAAAAUAUUUUCCUUCCUUUUCAAAUAUCCUUCUAAUAUAUGUGAAAGGAGCGGGGUUCAUCCCAUUCAUCAUGUGAAUAUUCACAGGAAGAGCAAUGUUAGGGUAAUCUGCAUAUGACUACUAAAGCAUAUAUCUGACUCAUUAUGUAUUUCUUUCAACUGAAUUUACUGCUUCUGAAAAAUGAUUUACCCAACAGGACUACCAGUUACUAGUGUCUUAAGGUAUAUGAACUAAAGUCAGAAGGAGAUGGAAGAAAAUUUUUAUAAUACGAUCUGAAUUUUAUUUUCAUUCUCUUCUUGCUUAGGAACGUUUUACAGAUACAUGUAAGGGGGAUUAAUAAUGAAUCCACAUCAGUUGAGAGAUCAGUUUCCUCUAAUUCUUACUUAAUUUCCAAUGAAAUCAGUAGGAGCCCCCUAGAUUUAUAAUAAUGUAUUCUCCUUAGAAAUCAUUCAAAUUAUAUGAAAUGUACCAGUUAAGUUGUUAUUAGUAUUCCAUUUAUUUAGUAUGUGGACGAGUUCACUCUAACAAUGUUAAAGGAUAAACUUUUUGGACCAAUUUUCAGUUAAUGAAUUCAAGAGAUUUGUAUGUUAUUCUUUUUUUGGAGGUAAUAUAGUACAGUUACUAAGAUAGGAUUUUGUAUUACUCUGAGUUUACAUCUCAGACUUAUGAUUUAAUUUACAUGAUUGAGAUUUGCUAGCUGUACACCUUUAUAUCUUUGUCAUGUAGAAAUAUUUUCUCAUGUCGUUAAAAGUACUUGUAAUUAUCAGCUUUUUUUUUUUUCCGAGAUGGAAUCUCGCUCUGUCACCCAGGCUGGGGUGCAGUGGCACGAUCUCAGCUCACUGCAACCUCCGCCUUCUGGGUUCAAGCGAUUCUCCUGGCUCAGCCUCCUGAGUAGCUGGGAUUAAAGGCGCAUGCCACCACGCCGGCUAAUUUUUGUAUUUUUAGUAGAGACAGAGUUUCACCAUGUUGGCCAGGCUGGUCUCGAACUCUUGACCUCAUGCUCCGCCCGCCUCAGCCUCCCAAAGUGCUGGGAUUACAGGCGUGAGCCACCGUGCCCAGCCAUAAUUAUCACUUUUAAUGACAGCAUAAAAUUCCAUUGAUAGAUAUUAUUUAUUGGACUACUGUCCCCCAAAUAAUGUGAAUUUUAAGUUGUUUAGAGAUUUUCACUGUGAUAAUAAUGUCAAGCUAUGCCUUCGCUUAACCUUGCAUCCUCCUCAAAGUGCUCCCAUAUCUCCAUUUCAUUCAUAGCCAGGUUUUCUCUUUCAUUUACUUGUCAAAUCAUUCCAAUCUGGAUCCCAUCUCCAUGACUCUCCCAAAUUAAAAAAAAAAAAAGUUUUUAUUAAGGUCACUAUUGACCUUUUUAUUGUCAAACCAGCUAGUAGUAAUUGACACAUUUGACCAUUCCUUGAAGCAGCUUUUGUGUUUUCUUUUGAACUUUCCUGACACUACAUUAUCUUUGUUUUCUUCUUAUCUUCCUAGCAACUCCUCAAACAUCUUUGCUGCCUCUCCUCUUCUACCUGACCUCUAAAUUUUAGAAUUUCUCAACAAUUGAUUCUAGGCCCCCCUUUGUGUUUCUGCAAUCACCAUAGAUAAUCUCAUCUACUUCAAGACUUGAAAUAUCAUCAAUAAAUUGAUGAUGAUCAAAUAUAUGUACCUAACCCAACCUCUCUUCUUACACUGAACCUAUAUAUAUCACUUAUUUGGUAUCUUCACUUGGUAUAUUAAAAACUGACUGUUAGAUUUUGAAGGGAAGGUGAGAGUUAAAGAAAGACACACAGAGGGCAGCUUGACAGCAAAUGCAGACUUUAUGUCUAGCAUAAAACCUACAGAAGUGGGGGACCAGCUUAAUGCCAGAGCCCACCGCUGCUUACAGGCUGGGCGUACUUAUAGGCAUGGGUGAGAGGGGUCUGGGCAGUAUGGCUUGCUGCUCGGCAGGAUAUUGAUAAGAUGCUCCCAUGAUGAGGUGGUUCUGGCCCUUGUUGUGGUGGGAUGUCAUCAUAGUAUUCCUUGGAACUUUGCCCAGCAAGAUAUGAUAGGGAUAUUUCUUAGGUUGGGCCUUUUUCCGCCUUGUGGUCAGGUGGUUAGGCAGCAUGUUUCUCACUGCCCGAACCCCUGUGAAAUGUUUUACUUUGAUCAAGGUCUGCAAAAUAGCGGGGAGCUUACAAAAUGGUGCAGUUUGGACUAACACUAACGUUACUGAAUUUUCCCUAAAACCUACUUUUCUACUUCUAACUUUUAGUGGUGCAUUCAUACCAACUAUUUCAGAGAACUAGCAAUGCCAGGCAAAAUAGUAUUUUAAAAUCUGCUUAAAGGCAUUAGAGAACCAAAAGACAGUGAAGAAUAACAUCACUAAGAUCUAAGACAGAAUGAAACUUAGAGACCUGAGCUCAGCAUUUGGGCUGCUUUUCUUAUAGGAGACAUGCCAAUUCAGGAUAAGGUGGUUGAGAGUCUGAGACGCUAAGUAACACUUAUAACAGCCUUGCUGCUGAGUUAGAGGGACAAAAACUGGAGACCAAGACUCUCCAAGGAAGUAGGGGAGGGGAAAGGAAUCCUAGUUAACUGACCAUACAUUGGGUUGUGACCCCAAGGACCAUAUCCAAAUUGUAAGGGUGAAGAAAAACCAGAUGCAGUUAGGAUCUUCUCACUUCCCAAAACUGGAUUCAGGUGACCCUUUGCUGCAGCCGCUACCCAGAGCAAAUGUAAAUCCUCUCUGGACUGAUCUUUUGAGUUAUUUUUAUAACUUUUCAUGUUUAGUGUUGGAAAGUUAUUUAAGGUAUCUGAGGAAACAAGACAACAUGAUGAAAAUCCGAAAGAAGCGACAGAUGAUGGGACAGAGCCACAGGGGACCCAGAUAAUGAGCUAUACAACACAGGGUCUAAAAUUACUAUGUUUAGUGUGUUUAAAGAUCUAAAACACAAGAUUGAGAAUUUCAGCAGAAAAUCAGAAACUAUAUAGAAGAAUCAAUCAACAAGUCCCCAACUUAAAAGUACAUUAAUCAAGUUUAAGAAUUCAGUGAAUAGGCCGGGCGCGGUGGCUCACGCCUGUAAUCCCAGCACUUUGGGAGGCUGAGGCGGGUGGAUCAUGAGGUCAGGAGAUCGAGACCAUCCUGGCUAACACAAUGAAACCCCAUCUGUAGUAAAAAUAAAAAAAAAAAUAACCGGGUGUGGUGGUGGGUGCCUGUAGUCCCAGCUACUCAGGAGGCUGAGGCAGGAGAAUCACUUGAACCCGGGAGGCAGAGGUUUCAGUGAGCCAAGAUCAUGCCACUGCACUCCAGCCUGGGCGACAGAGCGAGACUCCAUCUCAAAAAGAAAAAAAAAAAAAAAGGAUUCAGUGAAUAGAUUUGAUAGAAAGUGCAUACAGUGAAGUAAGAAUUAGUGAACUAGAAGUUAUGUCAGAAGUAAAUACCAGAUGUGAAAAACUAAGAGACAAAAGAAUAGAAAAUAUAGUAGAGAGUAUAAGAGACAUAGAGUUAACUUGAGAAGAUCUAACAUACACGUAACUGGAUUUCCAGGAGAAGAGAGAAUAUGGCAGAAGCAACCUGUGAGGAGAUAAUGACUGAGAAUUCUCCAAGUUUUUAAGACAUGAAGACCUGCAAGAUCAAAGCAUGAUAAAUAAAAACAAAAUUACAACUUAGCACAUCCUAAGAAAAAAUAAAACACAAAAAGAAAAUCAUUAAAGGAGCCAGACAAUGAUAAAAGACAUUACUUUUAAAGGAGGCACAAUUUUAUUAAACUGACAGCUAACUUCUCAACAGAAAAUAUGGGAAGCAGAAAUCAAUGGCAUGAUAUUUUCAGGUUACUGAAAGAAAAUAUCUGCAAUUUUAGAAUUCAAUACCCAGCCUUUCCCCAAAAACAAUUCUUAAGAAUGAAGGCAAAGACACUUUCAAACGCAACAAAUUUAAUAGCAGAUUGUCAUUAAAGGUGAUAGUAAAGGGUAUUCUUCAGACAGAAGGAAAAAGAUCCCAGAAAAAGGUUAGAGAUAAAGGUAGGAAUGAACAGUAAUUUAAAAAUAUAUAUAUACAGUUUAAGUGAAUAUUAACUAUAUAAAAUAGUCUUCGAGGUUAAAAUAAAUAAUGUUAAAAUGUGACAAUAAUAUACAAAUUUGGUGCAGGAAUUCUAAGGUCAGAAUUAUCAGAAAGAAGAUUAAAGUAUAAAUAAGACUGCUGUGUCAUCUAUAGGGUAACCACUAAAAGAACAGCAAAAAGCAAAAUAAAACAAUCGUAGAACUACAAAGCUAAUACAGGGCUAAAGUGGAAUAAUAAGGCAAAAAGGUAGAGAAAAUAUAGAACAAAUAGGACAAAUAGAAAUCAAACAGUAGAUUAGGAGGUUUAAAUAUCAGUUACAACAUUCAUAUGAAUAGACAGUGUACCAAUUAAAUGCAAAGAUCAUCAAAGUGAAAAGAAAGAAAACCCACAAAGUACCUUUAUGCAAGAGAUGUCUUAAGUAUAGGAAUACAAAGGUUUGAAGUAAACAAGAAUGGAAAAAUUAUAAUAUGAAAUACAAAAAACAAAAACGAUAGGGCAGGGGACUAUGGUGGCUAUUGCAACAUUAUUCAAUGUAGACCUUAAGGUGAAAAGUAUUACAAAGAGAGACAAUUUGUAAUGAUAAAAGAUUUGAUUCACCAGAAAGUUUCAACAGGUCUAAUAUUUUAAUGAUUUAACAAUAUAGCCUCAAAUAUAUAAGCAGAAAUGAACAGAACUAAAAUGAGAAAAGACAAGUCUGCAUUCCCAGAUUUUAAUAUACUCAGUAACAGAACAGCAGCCAUGCAAAAAUACGUAAAUAUGUAAAGAUUGGAAUAAUACUUUAAAACUUAACCUAAUUGGCAUAUAUGAAACAGAAUACCCAACAACUGCAAAAUACACAUUAUUUUCAAAUGCAGAUAGAAUAUUUAUCAAAACUGACCAUAUUCCAAGUCAUAGGAAUGGAAUAUAUUCUUUGGCCAUGUAUCAUUCACUUAGAAAUCAAUAAUAAUUUCAAAAAUAGAAAAAUUCUAUUAAGUUCAUAAAUUAAGAAAUACACUUUUAAAUAACUCAUGGAUCAGACAAUAAAUUACAAUGAAAAUUAGAAUAUAUUUGAACUGAGUAGUGAAAGUGCUACAUGUCAAAACUUAUGGUAGACGCCUAAAGCCAUGCUUAGAAGGAAAUUUAUAGUCUUAAACGCACAUUAAAAAAAAAAGAUUGAAAAUGAACCUAGUAGUUAAAAUAUUCUAAGAAUAGCAAAUUAAACCUGAAGAAAAUAAAGGAAAUAAUAAAGAACAAGAAUUAAUGGAGUAGAAAAUGAAGAUAAAGUGGAUCAACUAAGCCAAAAGUUGAUUCUUUGAAAAGAUAAUUGAUAAGUGUCUGGUAGACUGAAAAAGGAAGAAACACAAACAACCAAUAUCAGGAAUGAAAGGAUAUUACAAAUCCUAGAGUCAUCUGACAAAAUAUGUGCACAACUUCAUGCCAAUUAGUUGGAAAUUUUAGAUGAAGUGAAUAAAUUCUUUAAACUAUGGAAGAGCCAAAAUUGACAAAUGAAAAAAUAGAAAAUUCGAGUAGUUCCCUAUCUGCUAAAGAAGUGGAACCUAUAGUUACUUUAUUUGCUUUUCCAUAGUGAAACAACAAGCCUAGAUGGAUUGAUUCGUCAAUGGAAAGACAAUCUUAAAUUCUUACAAAGAGCAGUAGAAAUGCAGGAACCCUCCCCAACUCAUUUUAUGAUGCCAGAAAACCUAGAUACCAAAACCUGGCAAAAACUUUAUGAGAAAGGGACCUAUUUCAUUCCCCCCAACAUCAAUGCAAAAAUCCCAAACAAAAUACUAGCAAACUAAACUACACACAUACACACACACACACACACCCCUACACACACAGAAUAAUCACAAUCAAGUUGGGUUUCUUCCUGAAAAAGUGAGGUUGGUGUGAUAGUUGCAAAUCAAUCAAUAUGAUUCAACACAUUAACAGAAUGAAAGGAGAAAAAUAAUAUUUCAGUAGAUCCAGAAAAAGUAUUUGAUAAACCAGUAUCCACUCAUAAAAAGUUUGCUUUUUAAUAUUCAUCUUUAUUUUUCUUAUCUUGAGUAUGCACAUAAGAUGUUCAGAGUCAGAGAUAGAUUUCUUAUUACUCAGGGUAAACAAGUGCACCUGCCCACCUUUGCACUCGUCCAUAUCCCCCAGAGCAACCUGAUAAGAAACUCAUGGGAUUUUGGCUAUGUAAGUGGCCAAAUACUGCAUAGGCAAGGGACAGGGAAAAUUAAUUUUCCCUACUUAUAAAGAUGAAAGAGGCAGCCAUCCUCUUCCCUUCCUGAAAGAGUCUGCUUUUACUCUAUUCUUGUGGUAGACAAAGUCUCUCCAAAAGCCAGAUAGCCAACCCCAUGUGUCUCCAAGAGCUGUCUCCUACAUCCCAGGGAAUACCUAGGAAGAUAGCAUAUUAGAAAUGAGGAAAGGUCUCAGCACAAUAACCUAAGUUCCCACCACAAGAAACAAGAAAAAGAAUAGCAAAAUAAGCCCAAAGCAGGCAAAAGAAAGGAAAUAACCAAAAGCAGAAAUCAAUGAAACUGCAAAUAGAAAAAUACAUAAACAAAAAACUGGUUCUUCAAAAAACAAUCAAGAAAAUCCAUAAACCUGUAGAAAGACUGACAAAAAGAAAAAACACAAAUCAUUAUUAUCAAGAAUGAAAUGAAGAGUAUCACUAUAAAUCAGGCAGUCAUUAAAAAGAUAAUGAGGAAAUACUGUAACUUUCGGCUUAUACACAUGACAACUUAGAAGAAAUAAUCUGAUUCUUGAAAACCACAAACUAUUAAAACUCAACCAAGAUGAAAUAAUCUGAAUAUCCUAUAACCAUUAAAGAAUUAAAUUCAUAAUUUAAAAUCUCCUGAUAAAAGAAAUCUCCAGACCCAGAUGCCCUGGCUUCUUUGAGGUUCUUCCAUGUUGUUUUAUGUAUCAAUCAUUCAUUAUUUUUUAUCGCUGAGUAGUGCUGCAUGGUAUAGAAUAUAACAGUUUGUUUAUACCAUUCACCUGUUGAUGGACAUUUGUUGGUUCCAGUUUUGGGCUAUUAUGUAAAGCUGCUAUGAGCAUUCAUUUACAAGUCUUUAUGUGGACAUAAGCUUUCAUUUCUCUUGGGCAAAUACCUAGGACUGGGAUGGCUAAAUCAUAUGAUAAGUGUAUAUUUAAAUUUUUAAGGAACUGCUAAAAGUCUUUUUCAAGUUAAUUGUACCUUUUGACAUUCCCGCCAGCAGUUUAUGUGUACAAAAUGUAUAAUUACAUUUAUGUAAAACUAUAAAAUGCAAACUAAUCUAUAAUAAUGCAAGCACAUCAUUGGUUGCCUGGAAUGGGGUGGGCGAGGGGAAAUGAUUACAAAAGGGCAAAGGGAAACUUCUGGGGCUGAUAUAUGUGUUUACUCUCUUGAUUGUGGUUAUGGUUCACAAGUGUAGCCAUAUGGCAAAACUUAACAAAUUGUACACUUUAAAUAUAUGCAGUUUAUCAUACAUCAAUUAUACCUCAGUAAAGGUGUCAGAAAUAACAGGAUAUUUAUAUUUAAAUCUACCUUUGAAUUACCGAUUGUGACUGAGGUCUCAUGUGGCUUACUGGUGAAUCCAGUAGUUGAGGAAACGAAAGCCGUCACUUCUGCUAACUCUUUUACCAACUCACCUGCUGUCACCUUACACAACCCCAACUGUGUUUCAGCUUUGGAGUAAUGAACACACCAUUUUCUUCCUACUUAAAAGUCCACUCAGGAUAAUGAUUAAGAAAUACAUUGAUGCCGAGUAAUAAAUACUUUAAAAAAAGUUAAAUGUGAACAUUUGGCUUUCACAGCUCUUGACUGUCUUUGGCGAACCUUGACAUAAAGCUGCCUUUUCCAUCUUGGGCUGCUGACAAAAAAGCCUAAGAAAGAAAGAGGGUGUGUACAGAAAAUUACAUGCCAUAGAAAAAUACCAUACACAGGCCGGGAGCGGUGGCACUUUGGGAGGCCAGGGCGGGUGGAUCAUUUGAGGUCAGGAGUUUGAGACCAGCCUGGCCAACAUGGUGAAACCCCCGUCUCUACUAAAAAUACAAAACUUAGCCGGGCAUGGUGGUGCACACCUGUAGUCCCAGCUACUUGGGAGGUUGAGGCAGGAGGAUCGCUUGAACCCAGGAGGCAGAGAUUGCGGUGAACUGAGAUAGUGCCACUGUACUCUAGCCUGGGCGACACAGUAAGACUCCAUCUCCAAAAGAAAGAAAGAAAGAAAGAAAAAAAUGCCAUACAGAUGAAUCUUUAAAGAUUUUAAUUUAUAUAUACCUCUUCUACCAUUCAUUGGCUGGAGUAGUUGAACAGACAUCAGCAGGCACAAUGCUAGGCAGGCACUGGAGAUUCAGUGAUGAAUAAAACAAAACUGACCUGGAACCUGGCCUCCUGAAGCUUCUCUUCAUCUGUCUAAAUUCCUUUCUUUCAAGGCCCAGUGCAAGUGACACCUUCAUCAGGAAGGGCUUCCACAUGAUUCUAUCUGCAAAUCUCCCUUUUCUGAACUAUUAUGCUUAUAGUCUGUACCAGGCCACAUGACAUAUGUUAUUUUGUGGCAUUCUAGAAUUAUUCCAAUCUUUUCAUUCUUAUAAUUGGUGUGUUGUAUUCAAUAAAUAAUGUUGUUAUUCCAGUUUUCAUCACUGGUCACGCAAGAGUCCUCUCUUUAUUAUAUUUUAUCCCCAUAGUUCACCCCGUUUCCUCCCCAUCCUAAGUAACUAUUACCAUACCUAAAUAUAUAUCUAAUUAGGUUGUAUGUUUUCUUGCAAAAUGAGCACUAUCUUCUGUGCACAUAUAUUUGUGUAUGUGAACAGUAUUGUGUUAGCGUUGCUUCUUUAUUUCUUCACUUAUGACUAUGCCUCUAGUACAUAUCCAUGUUGUUAUGUAUGCAUUUAUUCCAUUGCUUCUACCCGCUAUACCUCAUCGUGUACCUCUACCACAUGUCAUCUUCCCCCUUUUCCAAGGACAGCCACUUGGGUGGCUUCCAACUUGCCCAACAACUAUUCUACAGUUAUUUUAUGUAUGUUACUUUGGCUCCAGCUCAAUUGUGAACUGCUUGUAGAUAAGGACCAUGUUUUUCUUUACCUGUUACUCCUGCUGAUUUCCUAUUAGUGCCUGUGCAUGUUUUCUGCUGUAAGGUGUUAAAUGUUAAAGUAAAAUUAAUAAUAGUAGAAGUAAGGAGUUGCCAGUGGAAUCUUCCUGAGCUGAAUCUAAUCAUGGCUUUACCCCUUACUAGCUUUGUGACCUUGACCUUGGAAAAGUAAAACCUUGUUGGUCUUUCUUCAUCUAUCAAGGUAGGUAAUACCAUCUAUCUUAGUGGGCUGUUAUGAGGAAUGAGUUAAUUAACUAAUACUAAGCACUCCAGUACAGUAGAAGACAUACAACAGGUGUUUAAUGAAUAAUAGGUGCAAUGAAUCCUACCUGCUGCUUCAAAUUACAGCCAUCUGUACCUGUCAACUUUUCUAAGAGUAUAAGCAUCUUGGAGGUAAGGUCAUUUCAAAUACUUCUUUAUAUCUGGUCAUUACCCAGCACUCUGCUUUGUGUGAAAUAUUCUAUACAUUUAUGUUGCUAUGGUUUGGAUGUUUUUGUCCCCUCCAAAAUUCAUGUCGAAACUUAAUCCCCAAAGCAACAGUAUUAAAGGAUGUGGCCUUUAAGAGGUGACUGAGUAAUGAAUGAGAUUAAAUGCUCUUUUGAAAGCAUUUUGCUCCUCUUUCCCUUCUGUCCCUUCCACCAUGUGAGGACAUACAUUCCUCCACUGUGGAGGAUGCAGCAAUGAGGUGCCAUCUUGGAAGCAGAGAUCAGCCUUCACCAGACACUAAUUCUGCUGGUGCAUUGGUCUUGGAAUUCCCAGCCUCAAGAGCCAGGAAAAACAGAUUUCUGUUGUUUAUAAAUUACCAAAUCUGUGGUAUUUUGUUAUAGCAGCACAAAUGGACUAAGACAAAUCUGUUAACUUAGAUUUUAAGCAUAUGUGCUAAAGUAUUUUAAAAGGUUAUUUUAUCCAAGAAUAUAGUAUGAGUUAAUACCUUUUUUGCAAGAUUCAUGGCAAUCUUUUAUUAUUUAUUUUUUAUUUCAUUCCAUGUUGGAAGCAAAGUCAUAUCUAUUAAAAAGUAAAAUCACAAAUUAGUCUUUGAUUAUUCAGAAGCAUAAGAAGAUUGCUGUUUUCAUGUUUUCCAUUUCUCCCUCCAGUGGCUUGAAAAGUACAGGUGCUCUUUUCAGUCAUGUUUUGUCUUAAAGAUUUUAAAAUAAGAAGAGUCUGCAUCCUGUAAAAGAGGGACAGAAACAUGGAUCAGUACCUACUCCUAUUUACUCCAGUUUUUAACAUUUAAGUCCUUCUGUUUUGAGGAGCUGUAUCAUUAUGAUUCACUAUUAAGAAUCUUUACAAAAGUUCAGAAACUGCUUAAAUUAGAAUUUAAAAAUCAUAGCCAAAAUUCUAGAUGUACACAAAAGUACUUCUAAUGAGUUUAGCAUCAUCUCUGGUUUAGAGGAGGUAUAAAUAGCAUUGGACUGCAAUGCUAAAUUCUCUAUAAUGACUUUUCUGGAUCAGCAUAUCAUACCUACACUGACUUGCCCUAAUAAAUAAAAACAAUGAGUCAGAUUAUGUAGAAUUGAGAUAUAUGGAAGAUAACUCUUUAAAAUUAUUUGUGGCCAGGCAGGCACUGUGGCUCAUGCCUGUAAUCCCAGCACUUUGGGAGGCCGAGGUGGGCAGAUCACCUGAGGUCAGGAGUUAGAGACCAGCCUGGCAAAACCCCAUCUCUACUAAAAAUACAAAAAUUAGCUGGGUGUGGUGGUGUGCACCUGUAAUCCCAGCUACCCGGGAGGCUGAGGCAAGAGAAUUGCUUGAAUCCAGGAGGCGGAGGUUGCAGUGAGCUGAGACUGCGCCAUUGCACUCCAGCCUGGCCAACAAGAGGGAAACUCUGUCUCAAAAAAAAUAAAAAGAAAAAAAAAUUAUUUGUGAACUUUUUGUAUAUUGCUUAAGGAAUAAAACAAGGCAACCUGAUAAUCCCCAAGAUGUGAUGUUUCUUUUCAGAAGAUAUGCAUUUACCACUUUCAAAACUUUGCACUAAGAAAGACAAAAUAAUAAUAAUGAUAAUACAAAAUUCAGUGUAGCCACUGUUCUUGAUCCCUAAAAAUAAUAAAGAUUCAUAAAAACAAAGUUCCAGACAUACAGACUAAAGAAGCAAAUUCUAGUUAACAAGUACUAUUAGCUUGAAAUAAGCUAUGCUAGCAUUUUCUUAACUUAGACGCUUAUCAAUAAGAAAAUUUAUAUAUAUACAUAUAUAUAAAAUAUAAAAUAGUGGGAGAGAGGAAGAGUACAGACUAUAAAGAAUGAGGUAUUAUGUCCUAAAAAUUGCUUUGAGAAAUGACAGAAUGCCCAGCUUAUAAUAAAGAGUGACAAAGUAGUAAGACUAUAUAAUAAGCAAUAUUUCAAAGAUGGUGGUAGGAAGAAAAAGGCUGUCAUUUUUUUAGAAAAACCUAGAUGUAAAAAAAAUGCGAGAUUUGCUAAAUGAUGUUUAUAUUUUACAGUUAGAUAUUCUCUAAACAAAACAAAAUAUCCUUCAUAUGGACAUUUCUGGAAGUACUACUACAGUGGGACUGAAAUUCUCUAGUCCCUGGUCCCUCUUUCCCCUUUGAAAAAAAAAUCACUUCUAUAAUAUAUUCUUUCUCUGCCCUAUUAUUUAAAUUGAGAAUGUGAACCAGUACAGACAUUAUGGAAAAUACGGAAAUUCCUCAAAAAAUUAAAAAUAGAAUUACCAUCUGAUCCAGCAAUUCCACUUAAGGGUAUAAAUCUAAAGGAAGUGAAAUCAGUACCUUGAAGUGAUACCUACACUCCCAUGUUCAUUUUAGCAUUAUUCAUAAUAGCCAAGAUAUGGAAACAACCUAAGUGUCCAUUAGUGAAUGAAUGGAUAAAGAAAAUGUGUGUGUGUGUCUGUGUGUGUAUAUAUAUAUAUGGAAUAUUAUUCCACAAUGGAAUAUUUUUCAGCCAUAAAACAAUGGAACUCCUGGCAUUUGUGAAAACAUGGAUAAUGAAUGGACGUUAAUGCUAAGUGAUAUAAGCAAGAUACAGAAAAACAAGUACUAUGUGAUUUCACUUCUGUGGAAUCUAAAAAGUCAUACUCAAAAGCAGAGUAGAAUGAUGGUUGCCAGGAGCCAGAAGAUGGAGGAAAUGGGGAGAUCUUGGUCAAAAGGUACACAUUUUGGCCAGGCACAGUGGCUCACACCUAUGAUCCCAACACUUUGGGAGGCCAAGGUAGGUGGAUCGCCUGAGCCCAGGAGUUUGAGACUAGCCUGGGCAACGUGGCAAAAACCCGUCUCUACAAAAACUACAAAACCUAGCCAGGCAUGGUGGUGUGCGCCUAUAGUCUCAGCUACUCAGGAGGCUGGGGUGGGAGGAUUGCUUGAGCCUGGGAGGUAGAGAUGGGAGUGAGCCAUGAUCACGCCACUGCAGACUCCAGCCUGGGUGACAGGGCGAGACCCUGUCUCAAAGAAAAAAAAUGGUAGAUAUUUUCAGUUAUAAGAUAAAUAACUUAUGUUAUUAUAAUUUACAGAUUCUAAGGAUCUAAUAUACCGCAUGGUGACUACAGUUAAUAAUACUGUAUAGCAUAUUUGAAAUUUGCUAAGAAGAUUUUAAGUGUUCUCACCACACACAAAAAAAGGUAACUGGGUGACAUGUAUUAAUUAGCUUGAUUGUGGUAAUCAUUUUACAGUGUAUAUUAGAUCAUCACAAUGUAUACCUUAAAUAUAUAUAAUUUUUAUGUGUCAAUUAUAAAGAAAAUCUUUGAUCAUUAAGGAAGCUGAAUAUCCUGCUAUAUCUAACUCAAGCUGAGAAGGGGGAAAAAGCACAAUAGCUAACACUUAGAACACUCCAAGUUGUGUUUUAAGUGCUUUUCAUAUAUUAAAUUCAUGUAAUUCCCAUAACAAUCCUGUGACUGGGCACUAUUAUCAUCAUUAAUCUCCAUCUUAUAUUAAUAGAUGGGGAGACUGAGUGAUAGAGAAGUAACUUGCUUUAAGGGCAUGGGGCAGAGCUGGGAUUUGAACCCAGGUAGCCUAGCACCAGGCUGCAUGCUCUGCCAGGAGGCUGUGCUUCCUCUGUAGUAAGGUGGCCUGUCCCUCUCAACUCUUUCCAUCACUGGGCACAAAGCUACUGCAUCAGCUGUCCUCCAUAUUUAAAACUCAGGUAUACUCUUUGAUGAAACUCUACCUUUAGAGCUUCUACCCACACUACCAAGUCCCAACAAUACCAAAACACUCAUAAGGGAUCUGGCCCAAAGCAAACUGUUCCACAUUACUACUUGGUAGAAAACGAAAAGCUCCUUUUUGAUUUUUCACACUCUGGACAUUUUAGUGUGUCAUGACCCAGUCUGAUAACCUUUUAUGUCUCUUAAGCAUUUUGUUGUGUUUGUAACUUUUUACCCCCUAAUUCAUUUUCACUGUCCUGCAAAGAGUUGGAAUAAAUUAAAUGUCUAACAA